AUGGUUCUUGCAGCGGCGGCCACGGCUCGGAGCGCGCCGCCGCAGCUGCAGCCGCCGCCACCUCGGCCGCUGCGCGCCGCCUCAGCCGCGGGAGCAGCCCCCUCCCCUCGGCCCCGCGUCGCCCCGGGGGCCCGGCCGAGCGCGCCCCCGCGGCUGGCGGUUGGAGGGCGCGAGCACGCGUCCGACACACCCCCCCCCGCCUCCGGGGUUCCCCGCUCCUCCACUCAGGGAGCGGCCGCAGGAACCAAGAAAAGUGGGGAGGAGCACAGACGCCGGCGCGAGGCUGGGCGAGGGGAGGGGAAGCGAAGCGCGCGCCCUGAGCUCUGCACGCCCCGCCUCCGAAUCCUCAAGAUGGCGGCCGCAGAGCCGCCCACUUCCCCCUCCCGCGGCCGCCACGUGACCCCUGUGGCCUCCGCGCGGGGUGGGCGGAGCGGAAGGAAGGGCUUCUCUGGAGAGGGAUCUGGUUUUCCGGGGAUGCUCCAGGCCUCUGGACUUAGGGGUUUGGAGACCGUGCGGAGGUGUCUUCGCUCUUUCGUGCCGCCCCUCAAGCCUCUUAAUUUAGGGAUGGACACGAAAUGGUUGAAAACCAUUCGUGAUAAUAUAAACGGGCCUGUAAACGUUAGCUGUGUGGGAGGUUACGGACCCCGGCAGGAGCGCCCACCGAAAUCCUGUCCCCAGCUGAAGCAACACGACCCGCAUCAGUUUACUUUCCAGUUUGCCUAAUUUCUAGAGGUUGAAAUUGAGGAUAGGAAAGUACGAGGUGGAGGUGGUGGGCCAGAAUCAAACCCAAAAUAGACGUUGUCAGGCCUCUGAGCCCAAGCUAAGCCAUCAUAUCCCCUAUGACCUGCACGUAUACAUCCAGAUGGCCUGAGGCAACUGAAGAGCCACAAAAGAAGUGAAAAUAGCCUUAACUGAUGACAUUCCACCAUUGUGAUUUGUUCCUGCCCCACCCUAACUGACAGGAUAUAUUCUCCCCCUUGCCCUUAAGUAGGUGCUUUGUAAUAUUCUCCCCCGCCCUUAAGAAUGUACUUUGUACACCUAUCCCAAACCUAUAAGAACUAAUGAUAAUUCCACCACCCUCUGCUGACUCCUUUUUCGGACUCAACCCGCCUGCACCCAGGUAAGAUAAACAGCCUUGUUGCUCACACGAAGCCUGUUUGGUGGACUCUCUUCACACGUUUUCGAGCUGUUUUCUGACUAAAGUACUUGUGGUCAUGGUGGAGGUCCUUCAUUACCAGGGGCCCACAUCAUGACCAACUGGAGGCGUGGCAAGUUUUUGUAAGAGAUCCAGGCAUGCCCCCUCCCCUGGCCUAAGUCCAGAAUUUUCCUAGAUGCCAAUCUCAGGGCCCUGCAUCCUAAAUACAAAAGUGGGCCAGGCGCAAAGGGUCACGCCUAUAAUCCCACCAUUUUGGGAGGCCGGGGCAGGAGGAUUGCUUGAGCCUGAGAGUUCGAGACCAGCCUGGGCAACGUAGAAGGACCUCCAUUUCUAAAAAAAAAAAAAAAAAAUUUGCCGAGUGUGGUGGCACGUUCCUGUACCCCAGCUACUCGGGAGGUUGAGGCUGCGGUGAGCUGUGAUCAUGCCACUGCACUCCAGCCUGGGUGACAGAGUGAGACCCUCUCUCAAAAAAUACAUCCAUAUAUAUAUAUAUCCAUUUCCAUACGUUCUUAUAAUGGCAUAUACUCAGUAAAAAUGUAUAAAAUUUUUACUAGUUGACUACUUUUACCCAGCUUCACAUUUUAUAUAAUUUAUAUAAAAUAAGAAACCAAUAACAUUUUAAUGAAAAAAAUAAUAAAAAUAUGCCAGAGGUGUAUGCCCUGUCUUUAUUAGAGUAUAUAUGGAUUUUGGUUACCCAUACUUUUGGUGGGACUUAAUAAAUGUGAAAAAAAUGUAAAUCAGUGUGUAUAGAUACUUGGAGUCAAUAAAUUUUAAAUCAUGUUUGUUA